GGUAGACGCGAUCUGCUGGCUACUACCGGCCUUCCCUGGCUGUUAAAAGCAGAUGGUGGCUGAGGCUGGUUCAAUGCCGGCUGCCUCCUCUGUGAAGAAGCCAUUUGGUCUCAGAAGCAAGAUGGGCAAGUGGUGCCGCCACUGCUUCGCCUGGUGCAGGGGGAGCGGCAAGAGCAACGUGGGCACUUCUGGAGACCACGACGAUUCUGCUAUGAAGACACUCAGGAGCAAGAUGGGCAAGUGGUGCUGCCACUGCUUCCCCUGGUGCAGGGGGAGCGGCAAGAGCAACGUGGGCACUUCUGGAGACCACGACGAUUCUGCUAUGAAGACACUCAGGAGCAAGAUGGGCAAGUGGUGCUGCCACUGCUUCCCCUGCUGCAGGGGGAGCGGCAAGAGCAACGUGGGCACUUCUGGAGACCACGACGACUCUGCUAUGAAGACACUCAGGAGCAAGAUGGGCAAGUGGUGCUGCCACUGCUUCCCCUGCUGCAGGGGGAGCGGCAAGAACAAAGUGGGCCCUUGGGGAGACUACGACGACAGCGCUUUCAUGGAGCCGAGGUACCACGUCCGUCGAGAAGAUCUGGACAAGCUCCACAGAGCUGCCUGGUGGGGUAAAGUCCCCAGAAAGGAUCUCAUCGUCAUGCUCAAGGACACUGACAUGAACAAGAAGGACAAGCAAAAGAGGACUGCUCUACAUCUGGCCUCUGCCAAUGGAAAUUCAGAAGUAGUAAAACUCCUGCUGGACAGACGAUGUCAACUUAAUAUCCUUGACAACAAAAAGAGGACAGCUCUGACAAAGGCCGUACAAUGCCAGGAAGAUGAAUGUGCGUUAAUGUUGCUGGAACAUGGCACUGAUCCGAAUAUUCCAGAUGAGUAUGGAAAUACCGCUCUACACUAUGCUAUCUACAAUGAAGAUAAAUUAAUGGCCAAAGCACUGCUCUUAUACGGUGCUGAUAUCGAAUCAAAAAACAAGCAUGGCCUCACACCACUGUUACUUGGUGUACAUGAGCAAAAACAGCAAGUGGUGAAAUUUUUAAUCAAGAAAAAAGCAAAUUUAAAUGCACUGGAUAGAUAUGGAAGAACUGCUCUCAUACUUGCUGUAUGUUGUGGAUCGGCAAGUAUAGUCAGCCUUCUACUUGAGCAAAACAUUGAUGUAUCUUCUCAAGAUCUAUCUGGACAGACGGCCAGAGAGUAUGCUGUUUCUAGUCGUCAUAAUGUAAUUUGCCAGUUACUUUCUGACUACAAAGAAAAACAGAUACUAAAAGUCUCUUCUGAAAACAGCAAUCCAGAACAAGACUUAAAGCUGACAUCAGAGGAAGAGUCACAAAGGCUUAAAGGAAGUGAAAAUAGCCAGCCAGAGGAAAUGUCUCAAGAACCAGAAAUAAAUAAGGGUGGUGAUAGAAAGGUUGAAGAAGAAAUGAAGAAGCACGGAAGUACUCAUAUGGGAUUCCCAGAAAACCUGACUAACGGUGCCACUGCUGACAAUGGUGAUGAUGGAUUAAUUCCACCAAGGAAAAGCAGAACACCUGAAAGCCAGCAAUUUCCUGACACUGAGAAUGAACAGUAUCACAGUGAUGAACAAAAUGAUACUCAGAAGCAACUUUCUGAAGAACAGAACACUGGAAUAUUACAAGAUGAGAUUCUGAUUCAUGAAGAAAAGCAGAUAGAAGUGGCUGAAAAUGAAUUCUGAGCUUUCUCUUAGUUAUAAGAAAGAAAAAGACCUCUUGCAUGAAAAUAGUACGUUGCAGGAAGAAAUUGUCAUGCUAAGACUGGAACUAGACAUAAUGAAACAUCAGAGCCAGCUAAGAGAAAAGAAAUAUUUGGAGGAAAUUGAAAGUGUGGAAAAAAAGAAUGAUAAUCUUUUAAAGGGUCUACAACUGAAUGAGCUCACCAUGGAUGAUGAUACUGCCGUGCUCGUCAUUGACAACGGCUCUGGCAUGUGCAAGGCCGGCUUUGCAGGUGACGAUGCCCCCCGGGCUGUCUUCCCUUCCAUCGUGGGGUGCCCCAGGCACCAGAACAUGAUGGGGGGCAUGCGUC